GACUCUGGGCGGAGCGGGGCUCGAGGCUGCUGGAGUCGCUCGCUGACUCGCCCUGCGCCCUCGCCGCGGACACCGGAGCUGCGGCCGCUCCCCGCUGUCCCCCAGCUUACUCCAAUCAAGCCUCUGCCCGCCAGGAACAGAGAUGGCAGAUCCUGAGGUAGUUGUGAGUAGCUGCAGCUCUCAUGAAGAGGAAAAUCGCUGCAAUUUUAACCAGCAAACAUCUCCAUCUGAGGAGCUUCUAUUAGAAGACCAGAUGAGGCGAAAACUCAAAUUUUUUUUCAUGAAUCCCUGUGAGAAGUUCUGGGCUCGAGGUAGAAAACCAUGGAAACUUGCCAUACAAAUUCUAAAAAUUGCAAUGGUGACUAUCCAGCUGGUCUUAUUUGGGCUAAGUAACCAGAUGGUGGUAGCUUUCAAGGAAGAGAAUACUAUAGCAUUCAAACACCUUUUCCUAAAAGGAUAUAUGGACCGAAUGGAUGACACAUAUGCAGUGUACACACAAAGUGACGUGUAUGAUCAGUUAAUCUUCGCAGUAAACCAGUACUUGCAGCUAUACAAUGUCUCCGUUGGGAAUCAUGCUUAUGAGAACAAAGGUACCAAGCAAUCUGCUAUGGCAAUCUGUCAGCACUUCUACAAGCGAGGAAACAUCUACCCUGGAAAUGAUACCUUUGACAUCGAUCCAGAAAUUGAAACUGAGUGUUUCUUUGUGGAGCCAGAUGAACCUUUUCACAUUGGGACACCAGCAGAAAAUAAACUGAACUUAACACUGGACUUCCACAGACUCCUAACAGUGGAGCUUCAGUUUAAACUGAAAGCCAUUAAUCUGCAGACAGUUCGUCAUCAAGAACUCCCUGACUGUUAUGACUUUACUCUGACUAUAACAUUUGACAACAAGGCCCAUAGUGGAAGAAUUAAAAUAAGUUUAGAUAAUGACAUUUCCAUCAGAGAAUGUAAAGACUGGCAUGUAUCUGGAUCAAUUCAGAAGAACACUCAUUACAUGAUGAUCUUUGAUGCCUUUGUCAUUCUGACUUGCUUGGUUUCAUUAAUCCUCUGCAUUAGAUCUGUGAUUAGAGGACUUCAGCUUCAGCAGGAGUUUGUCAAUUUUUUCCUCCUCCAUUAUAAGAAGGAAGUUUCUGUUUCUGAUCAAAUGGAAUUUGUCAAUGGAUGGUACAUUAUGAUUAUUAUUAGUGACAUAUUGACAAUCAUUGGAUCAAUUCUAAAAAUGGAAAUCCAAGCUAAGAGUCUAACUAGUUAUGAUGUCUGUAGCAUACUUCUUGGGACUUCUACCAUGCUCGUGUGGCUUGGAGUCAUCCGAUACCUCGGUUUCUUUGCAAAGUACAACCUCCUCAUUUUGACCCUUCAGGCAGCGCUGCCCAAUGUCAUCAGGUUCUGCUGCUGUGCAGCUAUGAUUUACUUAGGUUACUGCUUCUGUGGAUGGAUCGUGCUGGGGCCUUACCAUGACAAGUUUCGUUCUCUGAACAUGGUCUCUGAGUGCCUUUUCUCUCUGAUAAAUGGAGAUGAUAUGUUUGCCACGUUUGCAAAAAUGCAGCAAAAAAGUUACUUAGUCUGGCUGUUUAGUAGAAUUUACCUCUACUCAUUCAUCAGCCUCUUUAUAUAUAUGAUUUUAAGUCUUUUCAUUGCACUGAUCACUGAUACAUACGAAACAAUUAAGCAAUACCAACAAGAUGGCUUCCCAGAGACUGAACUUCGUACAUUUAUAUCAGAAUGCAAAGAUCUACCCAACUCUGGAAAAUACAGAUUAGAAGAUGACCCUCCAGUAUCUUUAUUCUGCUGUUGUAAAAAGUAGCUAUCAGGUUUAUCUGUACUUUAGAGGAAAAUAUAAUGUGUAGCUGAGUUGGAACACUGUGGAUAUUCUGAGAUCAGAUGUAGUAUGUUUGAAGACUGUUAUUUUGAGCUAAUUGAGACCUAUAAUUCACCAAUAACUGUUUAUAUUUUUAAAAGCAAUAUUUAAUGUCUUUGCAACUUUAUGCUGGGAUUGUUUUUAAAAAAACUUUAAUGAGGAAAGCUAUUGGAUUAUUAUUAUUUCUUGUUUAUUUUGCCAUGGCUUUAGAAUGUAUUCUGUAUGCCUCUCUUUUGCUCUGAUACUGUUGCUCCUGCUAUUCUGAUUGUGCAGACUGUGUAAUUAGUGGAAAACAAUCCUUGGUCUGACUGUGACUUUGGACAACUCAGUAACCCUGGCUUGGACCACUCUCAGGAGUCCAUCCUUGAGAGAGUGGGUGUAGUUAUCAUUUAUACAGUAAUCAUUGCAUUUUAAAAUCUUCUCUUGAAAGGAAGAAUAAGAGUGCACCAGAAUAAGAGCGCACCAGAAUAAGAGCGCACCAGCUAACAAUGUGAUACGGCCAUAUGUCACUUAAGGAUGGAGAUAUGUUCUGAGAAAUGUGUCAUUAGGCGAUUUUGUCAUUAAACAUCAUAGCAUGUACUUCCACAAACCUAGAUGGUAUAGCCUACUACACACCUAGGCUAUUUGGUAUAGCCUGUUGGUCCUGGGGUACAAAUCUGUACAACAUGUUACUGUAUUGAAUACAGUAGGCAAUUGUAACACAAUGGUAAGUAUCUAAACAUAGAAAAGGGACAGUAAAAAUAUGGUUUUAUAAUCUUCUGGGACCACCAUUGUAUAUGCGGUACAUCAUUGACCAAAACAUCGUUAUCCAGCAUAUGACUGUAUUUGGUUAUGAAAGCCAACUGUUACUUGAUUCUGCUUUUAGUUCUUAAGAGGAUCAGGCUUUUAAAUACUCAUUUACAAGUUUUCUAUCCUCCUUCAGUGUUAAAGUAGAAAGUAAAAAGAGUAUCUUAUACAUGCAUGAAAUUAAAGCAUAUACCAAAUGCA